GAAGAGGAGGAAGGAGGGCGAGCGAGGAGGAUGGCGGAGUCGGGGCUCCUGACGCAUUGUUUACAAUAACCAAGAUAUGAAAUCAACCUAUGUCUUCAUUGAUGGAAGAAUACACACAGAAAAUGUGACGUUCAGCCUUCAAAUCUAGGAAAUCCUGAUAUUGGUGACAUGAUCUGAUCUUGGCCCACUGCAACCUCUGCCUCCCAGGUUCAAGCGAUCCUCCCACCUCAGCCUCCCAGGAACUCUAAUGAAUCAUUGAUUGACCAGCACUAUUUUACCAGUUGGAAUGAAUGAUCAGAAAUGGGCAUAGUGCUUUUAGAUCCAACAUGUAACAGAUGGAUGUUACUCCAUGCUGAUUACUUCUUCAAGCCAGUACUUUUUUGAUUGUGUAGGAUCUUUGUCUCUUCAUCUUUGAAUUCAAUUACUGGAAAAUAAAAGGAGUUCAUGUAGUUUUUGUCCAGGCUUGAGUCACCAUGAGUAGUAGUUUAGGAAAAGAAAAAGACUCUAAAGAAAAAGAUCCCAAAGUACCAUCAGCCAAGGAAAGAGAAAAGGAGGCAAAAGCCUCUGGAGGUUUUGGGAAAGAGAGCAAAGAAAAAGAACCUAAGACCAAAGGGAAAGAUGCCAAAGAUGGAAAGAAGGACUCCAGUGCUGCCCAACCAGGGGUGGCAUUUUCAGUUGACAAUACGAUCAAACGGCCAAACCCAGCACCUGGGACUAGAAAAAAAUCCAGCAAUGCAGAGGUGAUUAAAGAGCUCAACAAAUGCCGGGAAGAGAAUUCAAUGCGUUUGGACUUAUCCAAGAGAUCUAUACACAUAUUGCCAUCAUCAAUCAAAGAGUUGACUCAAUUAACAGAACUUUAUUUAUACAGUAACAAAUUGCAGUCCCUCCCAGCAGAGGUGGGAUGUUUAGUAAAUCUCAUGACACUGGCUCUAAGUGAAAAUUCACUUACCAGUUUGCCUGACUCUCUUGAUAACUUGAAGAAGCUGCGGAUGCUUGAUUUACGGCAUAAUAAACUGAGAGAAAUUCCUUCAGUGGUGUAUAGGCUGGAUUCUCUCACCACUCUUUACCUUCGCUUUAAUCGUAUAACUACUGUGGAAAAGGACAUCAAAAACUUGUCAAAACUCAGCAUGCUUAGCAUUCGAGAGAACAAAAUUAAACAACUACCUGCUGAAAUUGGUGAAUUAUGUAACCUCAUUACGCUGGAUGUAGCUCACAAUCAACUUGAACACCUUCCAAAGGAGAUUGGAAACUGUACACAGAUAACCAACCUUGACUUGCAGCACAAUGAACUGCUAGACCUCCCAGAUACUAUAGGAAACCUGUCCAGUUUAAGUCGUCUUGGUCUGAGAUAUAACAGACUGUCAGCAAUACCCAGAUCAUUAGCAAAAUGCAGUGCACUUGAAGAAUUAAAUUUAGAGAACAAUAACAUUUCUACUUUACCAGAGAGUCUUUUAUCAAGUCUUGUGAAACUGAAUAGUUUGACCUUAGCUAGAAAUUGCUUCCAGUUGUAUCCAGUGGGUGGUCCAUCUCAGUUUUCUACCAUCUAUUCCCUCAACAUGGAACACAAUCGAAUCAACAAAAUUCCAUUUGGAAUUUUCUCCAGAGCAAAAGUAUUAAGUAAGCUGAAUAUGAAGGACAAUCAGUUAACAUCACUUCCCUUGGAUUUUGGAACUUGGACCAGUAUGGUAGAAUUGAAUUUAGCCACUAAUCAGCUCACAAAGAUCCCUGAGGAUGUGUCUGGUCUCGUUUCUCUUGAGGUUCUUAUCUUAUCAAACAAUCUUCUAAAGAAGCUUCCCCAUGGUCUUGGAAACCUUAGGAAGUUAAGAGAGUUGGAUCUAGAAGAGAACAAAUUGGAAUCCUUGCCAAAUGAAAUUGCAUAUCUUAAGGAUUUACAGAAAUUAGUCUUGACAAACAACCAGUUGACCACUCUUCCCAGAGGCAUUGGUCACCUUACUAAUCUCACACAUCUGGGCCUUGGAGAGAACCUACUUACUCACCUUCCUGAAGAAAUUGGUACACUGGAGAACCUAGAAGAACUGUAUUUGAAUGACAACCCCAACCUGCAUAGCCUUCCCUUUGAGCUGGCACUCUGCAGCAAGCUUUCAAUCAUGAGUAUUGAGAACUGUCCACUCAGUCACCUUCCACCUCAGAUUGUUGCUGGGGGGCCUUCUUUCAUCAUUCAGUUCUUAAAGAUGCAGGGUCCAUAUCGUGCCAUGGUCUGAUAUAAAUCUGCUGGUCCCACACACUGUUCAAAAAUAGACUGCCAUUAAUGUUUCUUAUCUAUAUCUGUAUCUAUUUAUGUAGAUAUUGGUAUAUGGCAGAUUUAUAAAAAUUGCAUUAUGUGUUUCUGCUAAUAGAGGAAUCAUAGCCAUUUAGAAUUUUUUUUAAAUUCUGUACAAAAGGCUUAUAUAAGUUUUCUUUGCUGAAUUUGAUGGAUGUUUUUCUGUUGUGUAAUCUGAUAUGCCAGUUUGCUUAAAACAUUUGCCAACACAUUAUGAAGUUAUUAAAUUUAAGGGACAGAGGUAGUAUAGUUAGAUAUACUUUCUCUUAGGAAAAAUAAUGGGCAAAAAUUUUUGUUGCAACUUUUCAUAUAUAUUUUCCCCUUACCAAUUGUUUUAUCCUUAUAGUAUUGUAGGCCCUGAAAGUAGAAUUUUUCUUUAACUUAUUUUGAGAUUUGAGAUUUAAAUUUUAUGUAUUGUUUACAGUCAGAGUAAAUCACUGGAUUUCUUUUGUUUGUUUUGAUUUGCUCUGUUUUAUUCAGUCAAAUCUAGAGUUUGAAUCCUCUGCUAAAGAAUUUGCAUCCACUGGUGUAAACAGUGAAAGGUAUUUGCUUGUUGAAAAAAAAAACUGGCAAAGUGAAAAGAUACAGUCAAAAAUCUAGAAUUUCUUUAAUUUUGCUUCUCUGACGAGUUGUGAAGCAAAAUACCUGAAGUGAGUCUUUGGGUAGGGGAAGGGUAUUGAGACCUUUUCUAGUAUGAAUAUUUUUUAAGUUUGGGGGAAGAGAAACUUGCAGUGAAAAGGAGUUUUUUCAUUCCUGAAAGUUGCAGAUCCACAAAACUAACAGGAUAAUUGGGCAAAUAAAUUACAUAUAAACACACACAAUCUAUAUAUGUAUAUACAAUGCUAUAUAGAUAUGUAUUUAUUAUAUCAUAAACUACAGUAGGUAACUUUAAGGAUUUCUUCCUAUCCUUGUACAAUGACAUGAAUGUCUUUCUUUGAAAACUGCAAUGUAUGUAUGUUUCAAGGUUAUUUAACAGUGUACUAUGGUUUUAUAUCUUGACUUGCCUUGUACAUCUUUCAAUUCUGGAAUAUCUGUGUCUAAGCACAAUAUCUUCACACUGUGCUGUAUUGCUGCUGAACUAAAUGCACUUUUCCCCACAUAUGGGGCACUGGCUUCAAACAAUUCAGUUCAGUAUCAUUACUUUUAAUCUCAUCUUUCCUUUCUUGGUAGUUGUUAAUACAGUUAUGGAAAAGAGGCACAUUGCAUAGAAGCCAUUGGGGAGUUCAGUGGAAGUUCUGUAAGAUGUGCAUGUACUAUUUGAUGCGUUUUCUUUGCUUCACUGCUUUUAAUACUUAGCAGUAUUGUUGGUCUAAGUCAAUUUGAUUAUUGAGGAGUCUCAGAGCAAGGUGCGUUCUAGAUGUCAUCCUAAAAAACACUUCAUAUAUAAUUAAUCACUAUUUUGUAUAAUUACAUAUUGCUGCUUGUGUGUUUUUUUUUUUUUCCAUUUAGUUGGGCGUUGUGUUUUACACAAAACCAUUUUUGAAUUAAGGCUAUGAUAUUAAGAUAGAAAUUUGGACUGUUGUUCUGCUUUUCCUGGCACUCAAAUUCAUGACUAGUUUUGAGGUCAAACCUAUGUUCGUAAUGAGAGAUUUUAUAAGGAUCAACUAAGAAAUGGAAGGCAGGUGAAGAUAUAAAACCCUAGAAUGCUUAAAUGUGCUGUAAAACUAUUGUAGAUGUCACUGGAUUUUACCAAGUAAUAUCCUUUCUUUUUUUUUUCCCCCCAUCUGCUGUGGCUUUUCAGUUAAAAUUUUGUUUAUAAAAGGAAUUUGUUUAUUACAGCUCUACCUA